GUGAAAAUAGUUAACAUAUUGGCUUAUGGAGAGCAAUCUCACGUUUAGGAUAAAUUUAGUCUGGCAGUGCCUACAAAUUAAGUCUGAGGUGAACUACUUUUGAACAGUUGAGUUAGAAAGUAUUUGGUAGCCACCAGGGAAAAGAGAUCUUAUUUCAAGAAAAUAAUUAGUGAAACUCAGUAAAGUAGAAGGGAGAUUAGAAGGAACAAAGGGAGGCAGAGAUGGGAUAGAGACUGGUUGCAACUUAACUAAAUUUGGAAGCUGGGAUUAAGCCCUUGAUUUAUCUUUUGAAAUGCCAUAUAAGAUAGCAUAAGAUGUACCAUUAAAUUCAGGAAACUGGGCUAAUAAUCAGAAAUAUGUGUUAGAAAUAAAGACCAUGGUAAAAAUGGAAGGGUUGUACAAGAGAAUAAAAUUAUUCAGGUUUUGUCUGUGGAUUUGCAUAAUGAUAUUUAUUUGCUGUGUGCCACAUGGCAGAAAAGGAAGUGAAAUAACACCCCUCUGUCCCGUCCUUUUCCCCAGAAAGAAAUCACUGGCUUCAUUUGUUGGUUUGUUUAGCUGGCAGCUUGAGUUGGUAGAACAGACGAGUAGAUUGUCUAGCUUUAGACGUAGGUAUUAGUGUACUGUUUCUUGAUCAUUGAUGUUUGAGACCUGGAAUUUGUAGCAUUAUUGAUUUGACCUCUGUUUUAAAUUUUAGCGGCUUCCACAAAGACUGAGUUAGUAAGGAAUACAACUAUGUAAGUAAUAUGUUUUACUAGCUAAUUUGUCUAGGCAAUUAUUUUUACCCUGUAUUCAUUCCUUCUUAAUCAAGAGUAAGGCAGGUAUUCUUUGCUUUGGGAAAUUCUUCUUUCUGUCCUCCCUUCCCUCACUUUUUCCAAAUUCUGGGCACAACAGCAGCUCUCUCUCUUCUGUGGCAGGUGUGCAUCCUAUUGGCUGGCUGGUAUUUCUUGUUUUUUUUCCCCCUUAUUCUUUUUAAAUGGGGGUGGGGGUAUAAAAAUAUGUGUAUGGGGUACAUGCAAUAAUGUUGUAAUGUUUCUUGUUGUUUAAUGGAUAAUUAAUUGCAAAAUAAUUGUUUUAAUUAUAACAUGUUUGAGUAAAUGCUAAAUUAGUAUUUUUUUCUAAUAUAAUAAUGAAUUUGAAAUCUAGCAUUCCUGUAACAAUGUGUCUAUGUUUGUCUGUCUGUGUCUGUCUAAUAGUAAUUAAUAUCUGUGGUCCGUACCUGGAAGAGGAAGUACAGCUUUAAAGGAAUAACAAAAGACUUUGUGUCUUAGACCCUUCGCAGGUGUUACAGUCGGGUGAAAGAACAUGGUGUUGGGAAAAGAAAGAGCAGUUACACAUUUGAACAGUUGGAACAGGUGUUUGGUCAGGGAGGAUGGGAUGCUCAGCCCUGCCAGCCUGUACUUAUUAACAGUAGUGGCUUGUACCAGGAGCUGGAGUCAGAUGGCAGCACUAUGGAGGACUAUUCACAGGAGGACUGGGGAAACCACAGUCAGGAUCUCCAUGGCUAUCCAACAGAUCAGGAAUUGGAUGAAAUACCUGUCACAAAGAGAACAUUAAAAAUAAAACAAGAGUCUUCUGAAGAAGCACAGAAGAGAGACAUCAUGCAGAAUAUUGUACAGAUUUUGGAAUCGGUACAGUUGAAAUGGGAACUUUUUCAGAGCUGGACAGACUUUUCAAGGCUCCAUCUUUCUAAUAAACUGGCCAUUUUUGGAAUUGGUUAUAACACCCGUUGGAAAGAGGAUAUCCGUUACCAUUAUGCUGAGAUCAGCUCCCAGGUGCCCCUUGGCAAGCGACUUCGGGAGUACUUCAACUCUGAGAAGCCUGAAGGACGGAUCAUUAUGACCCGAGUGCAGAAAAUGAACUGGAAAAAUGUUUACUACAAAUUUUUAGAGAUCACUAUUAGCGAAGCUAGGUGCUUGGAGCUGCACAUGGAAAUUGACUGGAUACCCAUUGCCCACUCCAAACCAACUGGUGGGAAUGUUGUUCAAUAUUUAUUGCCUGGGGGUAUUCCUAAAAGCCCAGGCCUUUAUGCCAUUGGCUAUGAAGAAUGUAUUGAGAGGCCCCUCUCACCACACAUGGAGCAAAGUUCCCUGGACCCAGGAAAAGAGGGCCGGGUUGACCUGGAAACCCUUUCAGCACAAGCCUCAUUACAGGUGGAAAUAGAACCCACCCGAAUUAUCUAUUGCUACCUCGGGAUUGCUGAGGUCAGGACUCUACAGCAGUGCUUAUUUUUACAUUUCCAAGCGAAUACCAAAACCUUCAGCAAAGAUUGGGUUGGUAUUAACGGGUUUUUGUCUCAGAACUGUAUUGUGGAUCCCGGAGUUUCCCCCAAAUCCAUCUACAUCAAAUUUGUAGAAGUAGAGAGGGAUUUUCUUUCCGCAGGCUCUUUAGUUGAGUGCCUGGAAAAAGCCAUUGGAUACCCCUUAAAAUUUAACAACUGAAUGUCAUCCUUCAUAAGGAUUUGGGCUCUUAGCUCCUUCUUCUCUACUCACUUCCCAUUACCCGGACCACCCCUCAUCCAGAUGCCGCCGUCAGACUCUUCAUGGAAACCCUUUCUUCAAUUGGGCCAGUACGACUUCUAAGGAAUCAUAGUAGACUUGGGCCAGAAAAAACAGACCUCACCUGAAAAUGCUCAUUUUGAGCAAGCAAGAUAUAUAGCGAACUUGCAUGGUGGGUCAGCUAUUUCUUUUUUAAAAACAGAAAAACAAUUUUUAAAUGGAUUUUAGAGCCCUAAUAUAAACAAAUGUAGGUACAUUCCAUAUUGGACAAAACUUAUACUUUGAGUUUCAUAUGAAAUUGAAAAAUUGUAUUUUUUUCACAAUGUUUCAUUUUUACACAUCUCUAUGUCUCUAUAUAAGUAAUAUUUACAACCCUGAAUAAAUAAGCAAUAGAUAAUGGCAAGUUAAAUCUUGAUUCACAGUUAAAAAGACUUUUUCAAUAUCACCCUUAGCUACUAUUGUAUAUAAUUUAGAUUUUCAUUUUUUUCACCAGCCAAGUGUUUUGCUAUUUCCAAUCAGUAUUGCUUGCAAAGACCUUUGUUUCUGUGAUGUACCAACUUUACAGUUGUGUUGCCAUUUAAACCUUUUUUUAAAAAAAAAAAAUUAAAGUAAUUCCUGGCC